CAUUUUUAGUAGAGAUGAGGUAUCUCCAUGUUGGCCAGGCUAGUCUCAAAACUCCUGACCUCAAGUGAUCCACCUGUCUCGGCCUCCCAAAGUGUUGGGAUUACAGGCGUGAGCCACCAUGCCUUGCCUCCCUCAUCUUUUAAAAUCAUUUAUGUGUUGGAGUAGAAAGGUUUUAUUUGUGUAAGUUUAUUAUUCGAAUUGUAGAAACCUUAUGUUCCCUUCAGUUCUACUUAAUCCAGAGUGUGUUCUACCACGGCCUCUCCUAGAGAACAUCAGUUUCUUCACCUGUAGAAAGGGGAAUAUGAUGCCUGCUUUGCAGGAUGGUUGUGAGAAUUAAGUGGGUUAGAGCCUGGGCAUAGGGCAAGGCAUUAGGAAUGGUUAGCGCCAAAAUGUGAGGACUCAUGUUGGGGUGAGGGAUCAGGUGAGAGCUCCAGAGUGUGGGUGGAAGAAUUUGGCUGCCAAAGGCCUACAUUUCUCCCCUCCCAGGUCUGAGCAUACUUUCCCCUUCCUCUUGGCCCUGGUAAACAGAAUUAGUCUCCUGUUUCCUCUUCACCACCACUCCUAAAGCAAACAGCCAAGCAUUUCCAAAGGUUGUUUUGCUGUGAGCAGCAAUGGGAAAUAAAUAGGUAAAAGGAUCUUCUGCUUCCUCCUCGUUUACACCCGGUCCUUGGGAGGCAAGAUAAAGUACGCAGAGAUGCCAAGAGUUGCCACUUGGGCACCAAAGGGCUCUAAUAAACUUCAUCUGCACUUCAGAAUUUUGGGACCCAGGUGAGAGGCCAAAGUGAGCAGUGAGAGGAAGCAGCAGUGAACUGAGGUGGGGGCAAUGUGGGGUGUGCAGGUGACAAGGGAUCCUAGAGAGGAAGGGCUGCAGGGCUGUCCCCACCUUUAAGAAGGGUGGAAGGCCAGAGCUGCUUUCUUUGUAUUAGAAAAGGUUGGCAUCAGAGAAAGCAGCUUAUGUUUAAAAGAUUGGGGCAAAUAAUUUACAUUCCUAAGCAUUUUGCAGAGUUACAGUUGUGAAAAUAAUUCAAAUUCCACCAAUUUUUCUUUUAAUCACAACCCCCUCCCCAACUGCCCACCCAGAAUUUGAGGCUAGACAAUGAUUGUUUCCCUUAAGUAUGCAAGUUAAAAUACAGAAAUACAUCUUGAAAAAUUAGUUGAUAGUAAUUUGUUGUUGGUGGUAGGGAACCCUUAUGUGCUUCAGGAUUUGGUAUGACGGAGUGAUAUGACUUUUUUUUUUUUUUUUCUAGUUCAACACUUCCCCUUAAACUAGUGGUACUUCUAGGUGCCCACUGCAGAUAUCCAAAUUAGUGGAUGAGAGUCUUAUUUUCAAAAAUAAUUUUAAAUAAUUAUCUAAUGCCACUCAUAUCUAACACAGGUAUUCUGAUCACUUGGAUUCUUGUAAGAAAAUGGUGUAAGAAUCUACAUUAAUGAGAAAACAACCAAUACUGAGCAGAAUGCUGCUGGGAACUCUUAGUUGGGCCCAUCCAAUGCAUGCUCCGUAAAUUUUUAUGUUGUUUGUAUGGUAUGCUGUGGUUUACAGUCUGGCCUUUGCAUUAAUUUGCCAUUGUUUUUCUCUCAAAUAUUAAUGAAGUGUAGGAGUGAUUGAGUUCUAAAUAGGCAUUUUUAAGGUAGUCUUAAAAUAAAGCUUUUCCUUUAAAAAAUAUUUUUUUCAGAAAGAUGAAAACCACUUCAUUAGUGAUUGCCGGCAAAAUCUCCUAAUGUCUUUCUAUAAGCUGUUUAAGCUUAGCAUUAGAAAUUAGUGCUAGAGGAUUUAAUUAGCCAGCUCACAGGAUGCAGUCCCUUUAAUUUAGGAUUUCCCUUUGAGAAAAUUAUGGAGUUGAAAAGGAAUAUGAUAUUUCAUACAAGUUUCCAUCUUGGGCCCUUAUGUUGUUUGUUCUGCUGAUCUGGAAAUUGUACAUGAUUUACAUUAAAACUUUUUGUUUUUAAUAUCGAUUAUUGUAGUGUGGGGUGUUAGAUUAUGUGCAAUAGUUCUCAGAGUUGGGAAAGGUAAAAGGGUUUUUUUGGGCAAUGAUUAACUCAUCUACUUUACCAGGGUUACAUAAUCAAGUAUUAGUUACUAUACAUUUAGCUAAUGCAGUGGGUUUAGUUAAGCAAUGAAUACAUUAUCAUGGGAGCAUUAACACUUUUGCAUUUUUAGACUUGCCUUUAAAAAAAUUACAGAAAAACUCCUCACAACCCUUGCCACCCUUUCAGCCAUAACAUUACAUUGCCUUGGUUUCUGCCUUUAAUUUCCCUGGGGGUUCUUUUUAUUUAGGAAAAGGGUGAAAGAUGUAUUUGUGUAAGUACUACACCAGUGCUUCUGUUAAAUUCUUUUUCAACAAAGAAUAUGUUACUUGGGUGCCUUGUACACAGGGCGCAUAUUUUUUUGGAAAUAAUGUGCCAUGAAAGCAGUAGUUUUUAGUGUGCAUGUUUAUUUCAUGUCUGCCAGUUUAUUUUAGCUUAGAAAUUUCCUAAUGCUUUGAGUUUAUAACAGUCUUUCAGUUUAUAACAGUCUUUCAGUUAACUGAGUGCAUAUACAUAAUAUGCACAAAAUGGCCAACUUUUAGAAAUUGUGUAUUUUAAAAUCCCUUUUUUUUCAGUCUGAUAUCAUGUGUCUCCUUGUUCCCUUUAAUAUGCAACUAAAAUUUAACCUAAGAUAUGAAAAAUAUGUUAAGAAAAGCUUAAUUUCUUAAGCUUAAUUUGGAACGUCAAUGAAGAAUUAAACAUUUGCUUUCUAGAAACCUUAAUCUUUGUUAAUGUGAAAUUAACAUAGAUGAUUUGAAUAUGUGUUCAUGUGUGAGGACUUUGCCCCUUCAGUGUUUCUCUACUGAGUCUUUUUGACCUACUAUAAGAGCUAAGUGCAAAUAAUGCCACAUCAAUAUGGCGUAGAGAAGAGUUCUUUCUUCCGCCUGUUGGCAGUGCAUUAUAAGAGCAGUUCUUCAACUUUCUGGUAUCACUCUUAAUAAUGGAAGUGCCCAUAGCGCUUUUGCUUAUGAGAAUUAUAUCUAGUGAUAUUUACUAUGUUUGAAAUUAAAAAGAAAAAAAUAUCUAUAUCAAAUAACAGUAAUAAACUCACAACAUAAUAUAUCUUUAUUAAAAAAUCUGCAGUUCUCAAAACAAAAUAUUUUAGUGAACAGGGUGACAUUGUUUUAUAUUUUUGCAAGCCUAUUUAAUGUCUGUAUCAAAAGAGAGCUGGACUUUGCUGUCUGUCUCUGUAUUCAGUUUGUAAUGAUACUGGAAUGUGAUAUCAUUACAUUACACAUUGCGUACUAAUGUGAUACUGGAAAACUAAACAUACAUUAAUGAAGAAGAUUUUAAAGGGUUAAUAAUGUCUAGAUGUAAGUAUUUUUUAAAAUAUUGAUCUUGUGGACCCUCUCAAAGAGACUUAGGGACCUCUUAGGGGUCCCAGGACCAUACAUUGAGAAUCAUUGCAUUAUAACAUUUUAGAAUCCUAUAGUUACUAGAAAAGAUUCUCCCCUAAUACUUUCUAGUUUCUCUCUGUAUGAAAGUAACACUCUUUUACAAAAUCAACUAUUUGUGAGUUGACAGAACUUAAUAGGAAAAUGGGGAAAGAGAGCUGGGUUGAGUAAAGGUAUAAGUAACUCUUUGAAAUACUUUGGUUUUGCCAUCAAAUAGCAGUGAUUCUUCUACUAUUGUCUGACUCACUUAACUGAGACAUUCUCAGUGAUCCCUCUCAUUUUCCAAGCCACCUCCACGGGCUAGACCCCUCCUCCCCUCAAGAUUCCAGUAGCUUAGAAAAAGAAAGUGUUAUGGGUGAAAGGGAAUGUGUCCACACCCCUCCCCUGUUUCUCCAGCUGGGAAGGGAAGGAAAGGGAAAUAAAAUUUAAUGAGCACUUUUACUAUGUGCCAGGUGCUUUACAUAUGUUAUUUCAUUUUAAUUCCCCAAACAACCCUAGGAGGUAUUUCUAGCCACAUUUUGCACACAAAUAAAGCAAGAUUCAGAGAGGUUAAAUAUUUAAUAUAAGAUAUGUAGCAUUUAAGUGGCAGAACCUGAUCCAAACCAAAGUCUAUUCCCAAGGACUAUACAACACCGUGCCUUGGUUUGUGGUUUGUUUUUCUUCAGUUCCUGCAGAUUAAAAAUGGGGAUUCUAACAUUUUAUUGGGUUCUGUGACAGCAUGAUGAUAAAACAGUUUGACUGCUCUGUGAAGCUCUUGUGGAAUUAACUGUCUUUCACAGAUUAUGUUUUAUAAAGUCAAAUAAAUAUUUUAAGAAAAGGUUUAUAUAAUUUAUGUUUUAGUUCUACAGUUAAUUAUCUGUGUUUUUCCACAGAGCGCAGGAUUGUCCCUUUUUGUAUGCUCAAUUCUGUUAUAUAGAACAGCUAACUAUCCUAGAGGAAGAUUCUGCAUUUGCAGCCCUAAAACAGCUGGUCAUCAUAGUUUGUCAAAACUCCGGAAAGGCAAAAUCAAUUCUCAGGAACAUUAUUUUGUCUUGAAACAAAACCUAAGAGGUUUCCACUUGAGCGGCACAGUGACAGAACCUGCAAUACAAUCGGAGCCAGAAACUGUUUGCAACGUGGCCAUCAGCUUUGAUCGUUGCAAGAUUACCUCAGUGACCUGCAGCUGUGGAAACAAGGACAUAUUUUAUUGUGCCCAUGUUGUGGCACUGUCUUUAUACCGCAUCCGCAAGCCAGAUCAGGUCAAACUGCAUCUUCCUAUUUCAGAGACUCUCUUUCAAAUGAAUAGAGACCAACUGCAAAAGUUUGUACAGUAUUUGAUCACAGUGCACCACACAGAAGUUUUGCCAACUGCUCAAAAAUUAGCAGAUGAAAUUCUUUCCCAAAAUUCAGAAAUCAACCAAGUUCAUGGUGCUCCUGAUCCAACAGCAGGUGCUAGUAUAGAUGAUGAAAACUGCUGGCACUUAGAUGAAGAGCAGGUUCAAGAACAGGUUAAACUGUUCCUUUCCCAGGGCGGGUACCACGGAUCAGGGAAGCAGCUUAAUUUGCUCUUUGCAAAGGUGCGGGAGAUGUUAAAGAUGAGGGACUCCAAUGGGGCCCGCAUGUUGACCUUGAUAACAGAGCAAUUCAUGGCUGACCCUCGCCUGUCACUUUGGCGGCAACAAGGCACUGCAAUGACUGACAAAUACAGGCAGCUCUGGGAUGAGCUGGGUGCUCUGUGGAUGUGUAUAGUUUUAAACCCCCACUGCAAGUUGGAGCAAAAGGCCAGUUGGCUAAAACAGCUGAAGAAAUGGAAUAGUGUUGAUGUCUGUCCAUGGGAAGAUGGAAAUCAUGGCAGUGAAUUACCCAACUUAACCAAUGCUCUGCCUCAGGGUGCAAAUGCCAACCAAGAUUCAUCGAACAGGCCACAUCGGACAGUGUUCACCCGAGCCAUCGAGGCAUGCGAUCUCCACUGGCAGGAUAGCCACUUGCAGCACAUUAUCAGCAGUGACCUAUACACCAACUACUGUUACCAUGACGACACUGAAAACUCCCUCUUCGACUCCCGCGGGUGGCCCCUCUGGCAUGAACAUGUUCCUACAGCCUGUGCAAGAGUGGACGCAUUACGUUCUCAUGGGUACCCCAGAGAAGCACUGAGACUAGCAAUAGCUAUUGUUAAUACAUUAAGACGACAGCAGCAGAAACAGUUGGAAAUGUUCCGAACCCAAAAAAAAGAGCUACCCCAUAAAAACAUAACCUCGAUAACCAAUCUGGAGGGCUGGGUUGGACAUCCCCUGGACCCUGUGGGCACUCUCUUCAGUAGCCUUAUGGAAGCCUGCCGCAUUGAUGAUGAGAACCUCUCUGGGUUCUCAGAUUUUACAGAGAAUAUGGGACAGUGCAAGUCUCUGGAAUACCAGCAUCUACCUGCACACAAAUUCUUAGAAGAAGGGGAAUCCUAUUUAACGCUGGCUGUGGAAGUAGCCCUGAUAGGGCUAGGACAGCAGCGUAUCAUGCCUGAUGGGCUGUACACACAAGAGAAAGUUUGCCGGAAUGAGGAGCAGCUCAUUUCUAAGCUUCAGGAAAUUGAAUUGGAUGACACACUGGUGAAAAUUUUUCGCAAGCAAGCAGUCUUCCUAUUAGAAGCCGGACCAUAUAGUGGUUUAGGUGAAAUAAUCCAUCGGGAGAGCGUUCCAAUGCACACAUUUGCCAAGUAUCUCUUCACCUCUCUCCUACCUCACGAUGCUGAAUUGGCAUACAAAAUUGCACUGAGAGCAAUGCGGUUACUAGUAUUGGAAUCUACUGCUCCAUCAGGAGACCUCACCCGCCCACACCACAUUGCAUCAGUUGUUCCCAACCGCUACCCUCGCUGGUUCACUCUAAGCCACAUUGAGUCCCAGCAGUGUGAGCUGGCAUCCACCAUGCUAACUGCAGCCAAAGGCGAUGUUCGGAGGCUGGAAACAGUAUUAGAAUCCAUCCAGAAAAACAUUCACUCCUCAUCACACAUCUUCAAGCUUGCCCAAGAUGCAUUUAAAAUAGCAACUCUCAUGGACAGUUUGCCAGACAUCACUCUUUUGAAAGUGUCUCUGGAGCUGGGCCUGCAGGUUAUGCGAAUGACACUGUCAACCUUAAAUUGGCGACGGCGGGAGAUGGUGAGGUGGCUGGUAACGUGUGCUACUGAAGUCGGCAUACAUCAUGGUAUCCAGCAGAGAAGUGAUGACCACUGGGUGUGGUUUAGGUGAUCCUCCAGAUGUGUGAGCAAUUGUAGCUGGCCAUAAGAAGAUUUCCUGGCUGCCCAUAAGCUGCCAUUUUGUGAGGCCCUUCAGCUAACUAUUUCUCCACUGCAGCAGUAGAUCAGUUCAGAAGAAAACUGUACAUUCCCAGCAAGAAUGCCAACAGAAACAAAUGGUUGCUAUUUAAAAUAAAUAGUGGUUAAACGUUCUUUUUUCAUAUUUGCAUCAGAAAGGGAUACAUACUUCAUGCUGAGAAAACACUGCCAUCCCAGUGUUUAGAUAUGACACAGCAUAUACUAUAAAAUUAUUAUUUUUCUUUCACUAACGUAUAAUGGUUUUUUUAUUUUGGAAAAAGGGAAGCUGGUCUCAAUAUAAAGAUUAUCUUUACAUCAUUAAAGUCAUGCUUUAGUGAAGCAAAACAAAAAUAAUACUAAUUUAAGAACUGCCACACAACUUCUUUGCCCCUGCCCCAACAUAUAAACCUGAUUUCUCUCUGAGACCUAGUACCUUCUCUUCAAAUCAUUCACUUUUAGGAUUUUCCUACAAGUGAGGGAUAUUGGGUCUGUGAACGUAAAGUGAUUAUUUUAAAGACAUGGUCAGCCAUUUCCAACGUUUGAUUCAUCUGUAGGUCUGCUUCUAUUGACUUUGUUCUCUUGAUUAUGGGCCACAUUUUCCAGCUUCUUUGUGUGUUUUAAACUUUUGUAUUAUGUGUACUUUUACCUUACACACAAGCACAUAAGCCAUGUAAAGUCCCUGUUUUGGUGAGGUUGCAAUUUUUGAGCCUCAAAUUCUGACAGGAAGCCCCAGUGAAGUAGAACUCAUUAGCAAAAAGCCAUUGUCUGAAAUGGCAAGCAGCACAGUACAAAUACCAGCUACCAAGAGGAUUGGUUCUUUAUUAUAGCAAGUUCAUGUUCCUUUCAGGCAUUUCACUGAAUAACAAUUCAUAAUGACCUUAUUCUUAAAGGUUUCUCACAGGCACAUUACUUUACAGGAUUUUCUAGCCUAGCUCAUGUCCUAUGAUGGUUAACAAUGUAAACACUGGUUGUAAAAGUCAAAAUAAGGCAGGACCUCUGGGCAGCCUCCUCGUCAGUAAUAGAGCCUGUUUGUGUUCCUUGCAGGGGUUUAUGCCCUGGACAGCAUCAUGCAGACCUGGUUUACACUCUUUACUCCCACCGAGGCCACAAGUAUAGUUGCAACUACCGUGAUGUCCAACAGCACCAUCGUCCGCCUCCACCUGGACUGCCACCAGCAGGAAAAGCUGGCCAGCAGCGCCCGGACACUUGCACUGCAGUGUGCCAUGAAGGAUCCACAGAACUGUGCCCUCUCUGCGCUAACCCUUUGUGAAAAGGAUCACAUAGCUUUUGAGACGGCGUACCAAAUUGUUCUCGACGCUGCUACGACUGGCAUGAGCUAUACACAGCUCUUUACAAUAGCACGGUACAUGGAGCACCGCGGGUACCCCAUGAGGGCCUACAAGCUGGCCACCCUGGCCAUGACCCAUCUCAACCUGAGCUACAAUCAGGACACACACCCUGCCAUUAAUGAUGUUUUGUGGGCCUGUGCGCUUAGCCACUCCCUUGGUAAAAAUGAGCUUGCAGCUAUAAUACCUCUGGUGGUCAAGAGUGUCAAGUGUGCAACGGUACUGUCAGACAUUUUGCGCAGAUGCACUCUGACCACUCCUGGCAUGGUGGGACUUCAUGGGAGGAGGAACUCUGGUAAGCUCAUGUCACUGGACAAAGCCCCCUUGAGGCAACUCUUGGAUGCCACGAUCGGGGCCUACAUCAACACAACGCACUCACGGCUCACACACAUCAGUCCUCGGCACUAUAGUGAGUUUAUAGAGUUCCUCAGCAAAGCCCGAGAGACCUUCUUAAUGGCGCAUGAUGGACACAUUCAGUUUACACAGUUUAUUGACAACCUGAAACAAAUCUACAAAGGCAAAAAGAAACUGAUGAUGUUGGUUCGGGAGAGGUUUGGUUGAUAGAUCUUGUAUGAAUGGGGUGGGGGGUGGGGAUGGGAGGGAUGGUUUGUUUUUACUUGAGCCUGCCUUUGUACCCUUUUUAACUUAAAGAACAGAGCCACACCGGUAUUAUAUGUGUAUAGUUAUAUUGCGUUUGCAGACUAAAUUGUCAUGUUGUGAAAGUUUGUGUGUUUUUUAUUUUUUCCCUAUUUCUUUCUUUCCUUUAUUUUAUUAUUUUUUUUAAUUUUUUUUUUCUGGUUUUGUAUGAGAGAGAGGUUAAAAAGGUUUGGUUUACACUGAGUAUAUGUUGUCAAGUGGCAAAAGUCCACAUAGCUCUCCUGUUUUCUGUAUACGUUCACAGCCUCAAAAAAAAUAAUUGAAAUGGCUUUAAAAACCAAACAAAACACCUCCAUCCUGUGAUAAGUACCUCGAAUGGAUUCAGCUUUACUCCUUUGUAACUCAUCUUUACAUUUUCAGCAUAUUUAAACAAACCAACAAAAUGAAAUACUAAUAGUAAAAAGGCUGACCCAUGUGGCUUUGCAGUGCUGUUCGUCCAGAAGCAUGGCACACGAUGCUUGUGCAUGUGGAAACUUAGCGACUGUCAACAUACAUUCUCAGGGAUUUAUCCAAAAAAAUUAAAAAAAGAAUGAGAGCAUUUAUUGUACUGUAUAUAUAUUAUAGUAUAUGUCUGAAUAUUGAAAAUAUAACAUUAACUAAUUUAUAAAAAAUAUUCUAUGUAAUGCAAAAUACUUGAAGCUGCAGUAGCUUGGUUUUAAACAAAAACAAAAAAAAAACUGAGAGAAAACCUAUCAGAAGGACUAAAAGUACGCCUUGCUUCAGGGUUGGCUCAGGUGGUGAACUUCAUGCUGGGCAUCUAUGCAGAGCCACCUUUUGGAUUGCAUGGUUGGACUGAGAUCUAUUGGGAGAAAUUAUAUAUGUAUAUAUAUUUAUACAACUUAUGUAUACAUAUAUAUAUGUAUACACACAGACACACACACACACCACCAACAACCACCACUACACCACACAUGCUUAUAACAGGCACUAGAAUAAAGAGGGACAACAAAAUACACAGCCAGAGCAGCAAGCCUUAGCAUUAAGAAUAUACAAUAUGCCGGAAUUGGGGUUCGUGCCUCCUAGCCUAGGAAACUUAAAAGAAAUAUCCUUUUGACACAAAACACAAAAUGUUUUCCAAAACAAUUGACAUAAUGAUACAUUACGCCUUUGCAGUGAGCUAAUAAUAAGCUAACCUUUGUGCACAAAUAACAUUAUAUAUAUUAUAUAUCUAUUCUGCAUAGGUAUUUUGACUUUGUGCAGGACAGAAAGUUGUGUAGGUAUGACUGUUCUACUUUUCAGUUUUCUUUUUUUUUAAUAUAUUUUAUUUUCUCUAGAAAUUACUCAAACAAAAGCAGCCUUCUAUCUUGCCUUGUCUUAAUGCUUUAAAAUAACCAAACUGGAGAUCUAACUACCAAACUGUUCAUUAUAUUAUUAAAUACCAACUUUGGUUACAGUAUAGUGUCUUUACUUUAGCUGAUGGUUCUGUAACCUUGUGCUUUUUAAAGCAAUUUUUAUGUUUUGGUGCAAAAGUUGUCCAGUGUCUCUUGUUCCCUUCACUAGAGAACAUGCUUAGAGGUAUGUUUGUAGGUAUUUUUGUUUAGAAGAACUAUUUCAUGCGCUCCAUUUUAUUUAUUAUAAUAGGUAAAAAGAAAAAAAAAGGUUGUAAUUCAUCACCCAUGUAAACAUGCUCAUGAAGUUGAAAGUAAUUAAGAUUUGAUACACUGAUAUCAAUUUAUUUAUGUAACUAAAUCACUGUUUUAUAAACUUGUUAAUGAUCAACAAUUUUUGUUUUGAUUAAAAUUAGUUUUUUGAAAGUUGA